ACUGGACGCACGCUGCGGGCGACAUUGUUUGGGACGCUGGGUUCUGCUUUUCCAGAAUCCUGCCCUUUCCAAAAGGAAGACGGUAUGAUUAAGUUCCAGAUUCAAGGGAUACAUGUGCAGGAAAGGGUGACAUUCAAGGAUGUGGCUGUUGUCUUCACCAAGGAAGAGCUGGCACUAUUGGAUAAAGCCCAGAUAAACCUGUACCAAGAUGUGAUGCUGGAAAACUUCAGGAACCUCAUGUUAGUGAGUGAGUAACUGAGCAUGAGACCACUGGACCUGUUUCCUCAAAUCAUCAUUUCAAACCAGAUAGAAUAUUCCAGUUAGACCACAAAGAGAAACUUUGGCCACUGGAAAGAAAACUCCUAAGAGAUGCAUGUGCAGGAGACGGGAUUAAAAACAACAUUUUGAAUCUUCAGGCAAAGGGGUUAAGUUACCUUUCGCAAGAAGUGCUUCAUUGCUGGCAGAUUUGGAAACAAAGGAUCCGGGAUUUAACUGUGAGUCAGGAUUAUAUCGUGAACCUUCAAGAAGAGUGUUCCCCACAUUUAGAAGAUGUUUCCCUCAGUGAAGAGUGGGCAGGCAUUUCUCUUCAGAUUUCUGAAAAUGAAAACUAUGUAGUAAAUGCCAUUAUCAAAAAUCAAGAUAUCACAGCAUGGCAAAGCCUGACACAGGUUCUUACCCCAGAAUCGUGGAGGAAAGCCAACAUAAUGACCGAGCCCCAGAACUCUCAGGGAAGAUAUAAGGGAAUUUACAUGGAAGAGAAAUUGUACAGACGUGCUCAGCAUGAUGACAGCCUCAGUUGGACCUCAUGUGAUCAUCAUGAGUCCCAAGAAUGUAAAGGAGAGGACCCUGGUAGACAUCCCAGCUGUGGGAAAAACUUGGGUAUGAAAUCAACGGUUGAAAAACGUAAUGCGGCCCAUGUAUUACCACAGCCUUUCCCAUGUAAUAACUGUGGGGUGGCCUUUGCAGAUGAUACAGAUCCUCAUGUCCAUCACAGCACUCACCUAGGAGAAAAAUCUUAUAAAUGUGACCAGUAUGGAAAGAACUUUAGUCAGAGCCAAGAUCUUAUCGUUCAUUGUAAAACUCACUCUGGCAAGACUCCCUAUGAAUUCCACGAAUGGCCUAUGGGCUGCAAACAGAGCUCAGACCUUCCCAGAUAUCAGAAAGUCUCCUCAGGAGACAAACCCUACAAAUGUAAAGAAUGUGGCAAGGGCUUCAGGCGCAGCUCUUCCCUUCACAACCAUCAUCGAGUCCACACAGGGGAGAUGCCCUACAAAUGCGAUGAAUGUGGGAAAGGGUUUGGAUUUAGGUCACUUCUUUGUAUUCAUCAGGGAGUACACACAGGGAAAAAGCCCUAUAAAUGUGAAGAGUGUGGGAAGGGCUUUGAUCAGAGCUCCAACCUUCUUGUCCAUCAGAGAGUCCACACUGGAGAGAAGCCCUACAAAUGCAGUGAGUGUGGCAAGUGCUUUAGUUCAAGCUCCGUUCUUCAAGUCCACUGGAGGUUUCACACAGGGGAGAAACCAUAUAGGUGUGGUGAGUGUGGAAAGGGCUUCAGCCAAUGUACACACCUUCACAUUCACCAGAGAGUCCACACAGGGGAGAAACCAUACAAAUGCAAUGUGUGUGGAAAGGAUUUUGCGUAUAGCUCUGUUCUUCACACUCAUCAGAGAGUUCACACUGGAGAAAAACCAUAUAAAUGUGAAGUGUGUGGAAAGUGCUUCAGUUACAGUUCAUAUUUUCACUUACAUCAAAGAGAUCACAUCAGAGAGAAACCAUAUAAAUGUGAUGAGUGUGGUAAAGGCUUCAGCCGGAAUUCAGAUCUUAAUGUUCACCUCAGAGUCCACACAGGAGAGAGGCCCUAUAAGUGUAAGGCAUGUGGUAAGGGCUUCAGUCGUAAUUCAUACCUCCUUGCCCAUCAGAGAGUGCAUAUAGAUGAGACACAGUACACACACUGUGAGCGUGGAAAGGACCUUCUGACUCAUCAAAGACUACAUGAGCAGAGAGAAACAUUAUAAAUGUAGUAAGUCAGGGUUCAAUUAGUAAAACAGAAGCCACACUGUAUUCCAGAUGAUAGAGGCUUACUCAGCCUGUGGGAGGGCUAGGGGAGCAAAAGACAGGGACACUGCCAUCGAUAAUGUCAGCCUGCAGCACUGAAGUGUGCCAGGCAAGGACUGUGGAUUUCAAGAACUUCUGUGAAGCUCCCAUCAACUGCUGUAUGCUACAAUGGCAAAGAGGUUACUUUUGACAAAUGGGUGGUUUGUGGUAGUGGUUGUAGUUAGUGGUCAAAUUUCCAUUAAAGGGUGUGUCCAGGAAGGAAAUUCUAAUUGGGAUGAUCAUGGUAAGGUCUUCAGUUCAGCCAACGUCUUUAGAUUUUUUUUUAGUCCCCAGUAGAAAAAUACUCUCUGUAUGAAGAACAUUCAAAAGUGUGCUCAAAAAUGAAACCCAUGCUCUUACUAUGAAAGAACGUUAGUACCCAGGUUUUCCAUGAGAUUCUCUACACAGGCAAGAAGCUCCAUAGAAGUGGCAUUUGAAGGGUGUGGCAGAGGCAGUGCUGUGUUUAUCACACUGGUUCCAUUUCCUUGCAAAUAAGAAGUCUAUUUCCCAGUAACCCUUGCAGUUAAGAGUGUGCCCAUGUGAUUGAGUUCUAGCCAAUGGAGUGUGAGCAAAAGUGAUAUAAGCCACUUUCAGGUCUAGCCUUUACAAACAUCCUCAGGCUUCUCUAUCCCUGCCAAGGUGACCUUGGAGGCUGCUUAUUCCAGACUGGGUUGAUAGAAGGUCACUACUUCAUCUGUGUUGGAUUUCUUUUUAGAGUAAGAAAUAAAAGUUCAUUGUGUCUCACCACUGAGAUUUUUGGUGGUUUAUUUAUUACUGCAGCAUUGCCUAGGCUAUCCUGACUAGCAUGGAGGGAUUUUAUAGCAAUAUGUUUCAUUGUCAUUGGAGUCCACAUACAGAAGUAACAUAAUUCAGAGUUCAAAACUUUUAAAUCUUUAAGGCUUGAUGUGGCAGUGCAACCAUCUAAAAUGGUAUGGAUGGGACUUCUUCAGUGAUAACCUUCAUUCAUUGGUGAGUACACCAAAGAGAAAUGUUCCAGAUGAUAUAGCUGUGGUAAAACUUUACUGAAAAGUAUAACCCACCGACGUAAGAAAUCUCAUAUAAUAGAGAAACUCUAUAAUGUGGGAUGCUGAAUAGGUUUGUCAGCUCACACCUUAAAUGCGAUUAAAAAUUAACUAGAAUAGGUGUUCUGUGGUUAGUCUUAAUAAAAUUAAUUGAAUAAAAUCAACAUUUACUAAAGUGACCAACAACAUGUAAAAAACCAACAGUGUUCAUUGCAGACUGAUGCAGUCUUCUUCUCAGCAGACCUGUAUAAUAAUGGGUUUUUAAAGGAUGCUCUUUCUGUCAGUUUCCCCCCAAAUUUGUCAUUUAAUUGGGGAUAAUAGAUGAAUUCGAGAGGAGAUCUCUUUGCUUUUUUUUUUUUUUUUUUUUUUUGGAAACAGGGUCUUGCUGUGUCACCCAGGUGGCUGGAGUGCAGUGGCCUGAUCAUUGCUCGCUGAAGCCUUGAACUCCUGGCUUCAGUGAUCCUCCUGCCUCAGCCUCCUGAGUAGCUGGGACUACAGACAUACACCACCGUGUUCAGCUGAUGUUUUCUUUAAAAAUUGUACUUGUAGAGAUGGGGUCUUACUUUGUUGCCCAGGUUAGUCUCAAACUUCUGGUUUCAAGCGAUCCUCCUACCUCAGCUUCCCAAAGUGCAGGGAUUACAGGUUUGGGCCACUGCACUCAUCCCACAAGGUGUUUUUUUUUUCCUUCAAAAACAGUGUCCUUUUUUGUUUUAAUUGACUUAUAGGUUUCUUCAUUUGGAUCAUGGUUUAUUCCUAGUUUUUCUUGCAUUACAGUUUCCUGCUAGUUAUAGUUUGUAAACAGAACAGCCAUUCAAGUGCAAAUAAAACCAUCCCUGAAGUGUCAUUUUCUUACUGAUCAGGUGGAUAAUAGUGAAAUAUUUUAAAAAUUCUAUGUCAGUAGAAAUGAGGAAAUGAGUGUUCUUACAUAAGUUGGUGGGGGAAAGAAAAACAGGUACAAAGUUGCUGGAGAGGAUCUUGUCUAUAUGUAUCAUAUGUACAAUGUGCAUUGUCUUUGAGCCAAUGAUCCUGCUUCUCAGAAUGUAUUUUUAGGAUGUAAUUACAUGAGUGGGGAAAAUAUGGUUUCAGAAAGAAAUAUGUUCUAAGAAUUUUGCAAUGAGAAGACUGUAAACAACCUGAAGGUUCAUGUAUAAGAGAUUGAGUAAAUUAGGGCAUCCCAUAUAAUGGAAUAACAUGGCUCCAUCAACAAUGAUCUAGACCUAUAAAAAUGUCCACAUGUUAUUGUCCAUGUCCACCACAUACUCCAGUACUCCUACUUGCAAACAUUAAGUUAGAGAAAAAAUCCGGGAUACACAUUAUCCUAGGAAGCUUUUGGGGUUUAGAAUGGGUGCAACAUUCCUUCAUGACAGAAUCAGCCCUCAGUGUUGGUGGAGGUGUCCCAGGCAAUCCUCUAGUUUGGCCGGGAGCAGCGCUUGCAUAUCACAUUAAGCUUUUUAAAUAUAUGAUGCUAACAGGAAUGUCUCCCUACUUCACAAAAUUGUUUGCUUUUCCUCUUGUAGCAAAGUAGCAUGGAAAAAGCAGAAAUUAGUCUAGCUCCCAAUCAGUGGGAGCCAAUCUCAUUUACAAAUGAAGAUGCAGAGAUCCUAAAUAAAUAUGAGCAUGUCAAAUCCAAUGAUUUGAUAAAAGCGUAACAGACUCGCUCAUGUAUAAUUUAUCCUAAAUAUGCUUAUCAGCUUCUGCCUCAUAACACACACAAGAACUGAGUAGCUCUAAAUACAUAUUUAUUUAGCUCAUGAUGUGUGAGCUGGCAAGUUCAACUGGGCUUAGCUGGGCAGUUCUGGUGUGGGACAUGCUAGAUUAUCUUAACUGGGCUUUGUACAUGCAUCUGCAGUCAGCUGAUGGUUCAUCUGGGCCUGGCUGUUUUAUGAUGGUCAUAGAUGAGACAACGAAGUUCUCUCUGUCAUCAUGGUCUCUCACCCUCCAGAAGACCAAUCGAGGGUUGGUCCCAUAGUGCCAGGGUUUCAAGGGCAAAAGCUGUGAUCUCUUAAGGCCUCAUCAGGGAACAGGCUCAAUGAUACUUUCACCACAUUUUAAUGAUUAAAGCAAGUCACAACACUGGCCCAGAUUCAUGGGGUGAGAUUAAGACAAAAUAAAAAAUGUUGAGACAUAAUCAUUGGAAGGAAAAGGAAGAUACUAUUUUUAUGCUAGAGAAUAAUGUUAUUUACUUAUAAAAUUCAAAUCCACCUGUAAAAUUUGACCAAUUGAAGGCUGUUUUAAAAUUAUCGGGUCAACAAAUUGGUUUCACACGAAAUUGGCAUGUGAAAAUUCAUAGCAUUACUAUGUAAGAGUCUUUUAUAAAAUGUAGCCAAAAUGUUUCAUUCACAAUAACAAUUGUGUGCAAUGACCAGAAUUGUCCAAAGGUAAUUCUGGGAGUUCCCUUUGGGAUGCCUAGGUGAGGAGCUAUCUGGGGCCUCAGACUCCCACAUUCUUCAGUGGGAAGGGCUUUACAUGAACUCAACUUCCCAGCGGCUUUCUCUUCCUGAUGGGAGGUGUUAGAACCUGGCUUUCUCAUGCAACUUCUGUGAAGCUCUGACAACUAAAGCCAGAUUGUCUGCUUUAGUUAAGUAGUCCAGAUUACCUGCAUAGUCAAUUUGUUCCCUCACCAACAUGGAUGCCUUCACAAUUGCUCUUUAAGAAGGAUAAAAACAUAGCGGUGAGGUGUGGUCUAUUUCCUGCUUCACCCAGGCCCUGGUGCUUCUUCAAGUGGUAUGAGAAAUUGUGGUCCUGUGCCUUCUCUUCCAGACCCUUAGCUUACAUGUUUUCCCUAUAAAACUUAGUCCUAAUCCCAGCACUUUGGGAGGCCAAGGUGGCUGAAUCACAAGAUCAGGAGUUUGAGACCAGCCUGGCCAACAUAGUGAAACCCCGUCUCUACUAAAAAUACACAAAAUUAGCUGGGCAUAGUGGCAGGCACCUGUAAUCCCAGCUACUCAGGAGGCUGAGGCAGGAGAAUCGCUUGAGCACAGGAGGUGGAGGUUGCAAUGAGCCAAGAUCGCACCACUGCACUCCAGCCCAGGCGACAGGGCAAGACUCUGUCUCAAAAAAAAAAAAAAAAAAA